CUUUUGCAGGCUCGUGGCGGUCGGUCAGCGGGGCGUUCUCCCACCUGUAGCGACUCAGGUUACUGAAAAGGCGGGAAAACGCUGCGAUGGCGGCAGCUGGGGGAGGAGGAAGAUAAGCGCGUGAGGCUGGGGUCCUGGCGCGUGGUUGGCAGAGGCAGAGACAUAAGACGUGCACGACUCGCCCCACAGGGCCCUCAGACCCCUUCCUUCCAAAGGAGCCUCCAAGCUCAUGGCCUCCUUAGGAGCGAACCCAAGGAGGACACCGCAGGGACCGAGACCUGGGGCGGCCUCCUCCGGCUUCCCCAGCCCGGCCCCAGUGCCGGGCCCCAGGGAGGCCGAGGAGGAGGAAGUCGAGGAGGAGGAGGAGCUGGCCGAGAUCCAUCUGUGUGUGCUGUGGAAUUCAGGAUACUUGGGCAUUGCCUACUAUGAUACUAGUGACUCCACUAUCCACUUCAUGCCAGAUGCCCCAGACCACGAGAGCCUCAAGCUUCUCCAGAGAGGUGGGGAUGGAACCAUGAAUUCCUCUCACUGCAACCUCUUUCUCUCACAGACUGUGUACAGUGCCCUGGGCCUGAGGGAUGCCUGCCGCUCCCUGCCGCAGUCCAUCCAGCUCUUUCGGGACAUUGCCCAAGAGUUCUCUGAUGACCUGCACCAUAUCGCCAGCCUCAUUGGGAAAGUAGUGGACUUUGAGGGCAGCCUUGCUGAAAAUCGCUUCACAGUCCUCCCCAACAUAGAUCCUGAAAUUGAUGAGAAAAAGCGAAGACUGAUGGGACUUCCCAGUUUCCUUACUGAGGUUGCCCGCAAGGAGCUGGAGAAUCUGGACUCCCGUAUUCCUUCAUGCAGUGUCAUCUACAUCCCUCUGAUUGGCUUCCUUCUUUCUAUUCCCCGCCUGCCUUCCAUGGUAGAGGCCAGUGACUUUGAGAUUAAUGGACUGGACUUCAUGUUUCUCUCAGAGGAGAAGCUGCACUAUCGUAGUGCCCGAACCAAGGAGCUGGAUGCAUUGCUGGGGGACCUGCACUGCGAGAUCCGGGACCAGGAGACGCUGCUGAUGUACCAGCUACAGUGCCAGGUGCUGGCACGAGCAGCUGUCUUAACCCGAGUAUUGGACCUUGCCUCCCGCCUGGACGUCCUGCUGGCUCUUGCCAGUGCUGCCCGGGACUAUGGCUACUCAAGGCCGCGUUACUCCCCACAAGUCCUUGGGGUACGAAUCCAGAAUGGCAGACAUCCUCUGAUGGAACUCUGUGCCCGAACCUUUGUGCCCAACUCCACAGAAUGUGGUGGGGACAAAGGGAGGGUCAAAGUCAUCACUGGACCCAACUCAUCAGGGAAGAGCAUAUACCUCAAACAGGUAGGCUUGAUCACAUUCAUGGCCCUGGUAGGCAGCUUUGUGCCAGCAGAGGAGGCCGAAAUUGGGGCAGUAGACGCCAUCUUCACACGAAUUCAUAGCUGCGAAUCCAUCUCCCUUGGCCUCUCCACCUUCAUGAUCGACCUCAACCAGGUGGCGAAAGCAGUGAACAAUGCCACUGCACAGUCGCUGGUCCUUAUUGAUGAAUUUGGAAAGGGAACCAACACGGUGGAUGGGCUCGCGCUUCUGGCCGCUGUGCUCCGACACUGGCUGGCACGUGGACCCACAUGCCCCCACAUCUUUGUGGCCACCAACUUUCUGAGCCUUGUUCAGCUACAACUGCUGCCACAAGGGCCCCUGGUGCAGUAUUUGACCAUGGAGACCUGUGAGGAUGGCAACGAUCUUGUCUUCUUCUAUCAGGUUUGCGAAGGUGUUGCGAAGGCCAGCCAUGCCUCCCACACAGCUGCCCAGGCUGGGCUUCCUGACAAGCUUGUGGCUCGUGGCAAGGAGGUCUCAGACUUGAUCCGCAGUGGAAAACCCAUCAAGCCUGUCAAGGAUUUGCUAAAGAAGAACCAAAUGGAAAAUUGCCAGACAUUAGUGGAUAAGUUUAUGAAACUGGAUUUGGAAGAUCCUAACCUGGACUUGAACGUUUUCAUGAGCCAGGAAGUGCUGCCUGCUGCCACCAGCAUCCUCUGAGAGUCCUUCCAGUGUCCUCCCCAGCCUCCUGAGACUCCGGUGGGCUGCCAUGCCCUCUUUGUUUCCUUAUCUCCCUCAGACGCAGAGUUUUUAGUUUCUCUAGAAAUUUUGUUUCAUAUUAGGAAUAAAGUUUAUUUUGAAGAAA